CUCUCUUUCCCUUGCUCCGGACCCUGAGAUCCUGGCCUACCUGAGCUCGGCAGACCUGUGGGGGCCCCUGGUGAGGAGAUGCUGGCAGAGUGGGGGGCUUGCCUGCUGCUGGCAGUGGCACUGCUGGGCCCAGGGCUCCAGGCCCAAGCCAUGGAAGGUGUCAAAUGUGGGGGUGUGCUCUCAGCACCUUCUGGAAACUUCUCCAGCCCCAACUUCCCUAGACUGUACCCCUACAACACAGAGUGCAGCUGGCUGAUCGUGGUGGCCGAGGGAUCCUCGGUGCUGCUCACCUUCCAUGCCUUUGACCUAGAGUACCACGACACCUGCAGCUUCGACUUUCUGGAGAUCUACAAUGGGGCCUCACCAGACAAGGGCAACCUGCUGGGGAGGUUCUGCGGCAAGGUGCCCCCGCCGCCCUUCACCUCCUCCUGGCAUGUCAUGUCUGUCAUCUUCCACUCGGACAAGCAUGUGGCCAGCCAUGGCUUUUCUGCGGGCUACCAGAAAGAUGUGUGUGGCGGCGUCCUGACUGGCCUGUCAGGGGUCCUCACCAGUCCUGAGUAUCCCAACAACUACCCGAACAGCAUGGAGUGCCACUGGGUGAUCCGGGCCGCUGGCCCUGCCCACGUCAAGCUGGUGUUCGUGGACUUCCAGGUGGAGGGCAAUGAAGAGUGCACCUAUGACUACGUGGCUGUGCUUGGGGGGCCUGGCCCCACCCGUGGGCACCACUACUGUGGCAGCACCAGGCCCCCCACCCUCGUGUCUCUGGGCCACGAACUGCAGGUGGUCUUCAAGUCCGACUUCAACAUCGGAGGCCGUGGCUUCAAGGCCUACUACUUCUCAGGAGAAUGCCAGGAGGUAUACAUGGCCAUGCGGGGCAACUUCUCCAGCCCACAGUACCCCAGCUCCUACCCCAACAACAUCCGCUGCCACUGGACCAUCCGCCUGCCCCCGGGCUACCAGGUCAAGGUGUUCUUCCUGGACCUGGACCUGGAGGAGCCCAACAGCCUGACCAAGACCUGUGACUUUGACCAUCUGGCGGCCUUCGAUGGGGCCAGCGAGGAGGCACCCCUGCUGGGGAAUUGGUGUGGACACCACCUGCCACCACCCGUGACCUCAAGCCACAACCAGCUUCUGCUUCUGCUGCACACAGACCGCAGCACCACCCGCAGGGGCUUCUCUGUGGCCUACAUCGGAGUGGUGCCCAUGAACGUGAGCUGCUCCCGCACGGACUUCCAGAUCCUGAUCUCCACGCAGGCGCUGGCCCCGCUGGAGCGGACCAAGGUCUACCUGGGCAGCCGGAGCUGUGCCGCCCAGGAGGUCGGCGGCAACCUCAGGAUCCAGGCCCGCUUUGAUACCUGCGGCACUGAGUCUCAGAGAAGAAACAACACUUCAGUGAUUGUCAGCGUGCUGUACAUCGACUUCUCAGCCGCGGGGCGGGAGGACAUCCAUGAGUACGAGGUCCGCUGUGAGCCACGGCGCAAGGAGGCUUCUGUCCACCUGCUGUCUGGCUCUCACUGGCUGGGGCCCUAUGCUGCCACUGCGGAGCACCUUCAGGAAGCACCACCCAUGGAUGAGGCGGAGGCACUGGAGGGCCCAGUGAGCAUGGUGGCCCAGGAUACCAGUGACAUCGUCUUCCUGGGCCUUUGCAUCCUGGCUGGAAUCCUCAUGGUUAUUGCCAUCGUGGUCUUGAUGCUGCUUUGAAUAGACAGCAUAGGGACCUGGCAUCUGACAUGCCUGGGAGGCAGCUUAGGGACCCAUAACAGGGGUGGGACGGGGACUUGCUGACUUGGUGACCAUUGGCAGGUCAUAUCCCUCUCUGAGCCUCCAUUUCCUAGGGACAGUCAUUCUGCCCUGCUAUCUCACAGGGCUGGCAUGAGGCUCAGAGGCGGGCAGAGAUGGAUAAGAGCUUUGUAAUCUGUAGCAUGCUGUGUAUGUAUAUGCAAUUGCUGUUAUUAAUUUUAAAGAUAUUCUGCUGUAGAAAA